AGACUCGGAGUCGAGGCGCGCCCGACAGCCGCAGCGCUCAUGGCGGGCGGAGGAGCCGGGGACCCCGGCCUGGGGGCGGCCGCCGCCCCAGCGCCCGAGACCCGCGAGCACCUCUUCAAGGUGCUGGUGAUCGGCGAGCUUGGCGUGGGCAAGACCAGCAUCAUCAAGCGCUACGUCCACCAGCUCUUCUCCCAGCACUACCGGGCCACCAUCGGGGUGGACUUCGCCCUCAAGGUCCUCAACUGGGACAGCAGGACUCUGGUGCGCCUGCAGCUGUGGGACAUCGCGGGGCAGGAGCGAUUUGGCAACAUGACCCGAGUAUACUACAAGGAAGCUGUUGGUGCUUUUGUAGUCUUUGAUAUAUCAAGAAGUUCCACAUUUGAGGCAGUCUUAAAAUGGAAAAGUGAUCUGGAUAGUAAAGUUCAUCUUCCAAAUGGCAGCCCUAUCCCUGCUGUCCUCUUGGCUAACAAAUGUGACCAGAACAAGGACAGUAGCCAGAGUCCUUCCCAGGUGGACCAAUUCUGCAAAGAACAUGGCUUUGCCGGAUGGUUUGAAACCUCUGCAAAGGAUAACAUAAACAUAGAGGAAGCUGCCCGGUUCCUAGUGGAGAAGAUUCUUGUAAACCACCAAAGCUUUCCUAAUGAAGAAAACGAUGUGGACAAAAUUAAGCUAGAUCAAGAGACCUUGAGAGCAGAGAACAAAUCCCAGUGUUGCUGAUAUAUGGCUUCUGCUUCUCUUGUGUGUGCCUCAGCUCUGAAGAAGUUCCUGAGAAUGGGUUACAGAUGUCAUGUUAGCUGGGAGUCUUCCCACAUGUGGCACUUCAAAAGGCAGCACCACUGGGCGCCUGCACUUAUUUGAAAAUGGAACUUUGGGAGAAGUAUCCCUGCUAGUGGCUCUGUAACUUAACAGAUGACAAUUAGGCUUUUGUCAUUGUUGCCAUCAUAUGGAAGAUAAUGUUUACAUCCUUUUAAACAUUUUUAUAUGACAAUUCCUCAGGAUUUGGUAAGGCUUCCAAGUUGUAGCUUUUAGUGUAAGUGCUGGGGUGGUAAUAAAAUGUUACCUCCA